AGUGAGAAGUUAGUGGCGCUGCUGGGACGGGGGAAAGGAGACGCUUCUUCCUCUUGCUGCUCUUCUCGUUCCCGAGAUCAGCGGCGGCGGUGACCGCGAGUGGGUCGGCACCGUCUCCGGCUCCGGGUGCGAACAAUGCUGACUGAUAGCGGAGGCGGCGGCACCUCCUUUGAGGAGGACCUGGACUCUGUGGCUCCGCGAUCCGCCCCAGCUGGGGCCUCGGAGCCGCCUCCGCCGGGAGGGGUCGGUCUGGGGAUCCGCACCGUGAGGCUCUUUGGGGAGGCCGGGCCAGCGUCGGGAGUCGGCAGCAGCGGCGGCGGCGGCAGCGGCAGCGGUACGGGCGGAGGGGACGCGGCGCUGGAUUUCAAGUUGGCGGCUGCCGUGCUGAGGACCGGGGGUGGAGGUGGUGCCUCUGGCAGUGACGAGGACGAAGUGUCCGAGGUUGAAUCAUUUAUUUUGGACCAAGAAGAUCUGGAUAACCCAGUGCUUAAAACAACAUCAGAGAUAUUCUUAUCAAGUACUGCAGAAGGAGCAGACUUACGCACUGUGGAUCCAGAGACACAGGCACGACUAGAAGCAUUGCUAGAAGCAGCAGGAAUUGGCAAAUUGUCAACUGCUGAUGGUAAAGCUUUUGCAGAUCCUGAGGUACUCCGGAGACUGACAUCCUCAGUUAGUUGUGCACUGGAUGAAGCUGCUGCUGCACUGACACGGAUGAAAGCAGAAAACAGCCACAAUGCAGGACAAGUGGACACUCGCAGUCUAGCAGAAGCUUGUUCAGAUGGGGAUGUUAAUGCUGUUCGUAAAUUGCUAGAUGAAGGCAGAAGUGUAAAUGAACAUACAGAAGAAGGAGAAAGCCUGCUGUGUUUGGCUUGUUCAGCAGGGUAUUAUGAAUUAGCACAAGUAUUGCUUGCUAUGCAUGCUAAUGUUGAAGAUCGAGGGAAUAAAGGAGACAUAACUCCCCUGAUGGCAGCUUCCAGUGGAGGUUACUUAGAUAUUGUGAAAUUAUUACUUCUUCAUGAUGCUGAUGUCAACUCCCAGUCUGCAACAGGAAACACUGCGCUAACUUAUGCAUGUGCUGGAGGAUUUGUUGACAUUGUUAAAGUGCUCCUUAAUGAAGGUGCAAAUAUAGAAGAUCAUAAUGAAAAUGGACAUACUCCCUUAAUGGAAGCAGCCAGUGCAGGUCAUGUGGAAGUUGCAAGAGUUCUUUUAGAUCAUGGUGCAGGCAUCAACACUCAUUCUAAUGAAUUCAAAGAAAGUGCUCUAACACUUGCUUGCUACAAAGGCCAUUUGGAUAUGGUUCGCUUUCUACUUGAAGCUGGUGCAGAUCAAGAGCACAAAACAGAUGAGAUGCACACUGCCUUAAUGGAGGCCUGCAUGGAUGGACAUGUAGAGGUGGCACGUUUGCUUUUGGAUAGUGGUGCUCAAGUGAACAUGCCUGCAGAUUCAUUUGAAUCUCCAUUGACGCUAGCUGCCUGUGGAGGACAUGUUGAAUUGGCAGCUCUACUUAUUGAAAGGGGAGCAAAUCUUGAAGAAGUUAAUGAUGAAGGAUACACUCCCUUGAUGGAAGCUGCCCGGGAAGGACAUGAAGAAAUGGUGGCACUACUCUUAGCACAAGGAGCAAAUAUAAAUGCCCAGACAGAAGAAACUCAAGAAACUGCUCUUACUUUGGCUUGCUGUGGAGGAUUUUCUGAAGUUGCAGACUUUCUUAUUAAGGCAGGGGCUGAUAUAGAACUUGGCUGCUCCACACCUCUGAUGGAGGCAUCUCAGGAGGGACACCUGGAAUUGGUUAAAUAUUUGCUGGCUUCUGGCGCUAAUGUGCAUGCUACAACAGCAACAGGAGACACAGCCUUAACCUAUGCUUGUGAAAAUGGACAUACGGAUGUUGCAGAUGUUUUACUUCAAGCAGGGGCUGAUUUAGAACAUGAAUCUGAAGGUGGAAGAACACCUUUGAUGAAAGCUGCAAGAGCUGGUCAUUUGUGCACUGUGCAGUUUCUUAUUAGCAAAGGUGCCAAUGUUAACAGGGCUACAGCCAAUAAUGAUCAUACAGUAGUGUCGCUGGCAUGUGCAGGAGGCCACCUGGCAGUUGUUGAGCUUCUCUUGGCUCAUGGGGCUGACCCUACUCAUCGACUCAAGGAUGGUUCAACAAUGCUCAUUGAAGCUGCAAAGGGUGGCCAUACUAAUGUAGUUUCUUAUCUGUUGGAUUAUCCAAAUAAUGUUCUGUCAGUUCCCACCACAGAUGUGUCUCAGCUCCCUCCACCUUCUCAAGAUCAGUCUCAGGUGCCACGUGUGCCAACGCAUACACUUGCCAUGGUUGUACCUCCCCAGGAACCUGACAGAACUUCACAGGAGAACUCUCCUGCCCUUUUAGGAGUGCAAAAAGGUACAUCCAAGCAGAAGUCCAGUUCCCUCCAGGUAGCAGAUCAGGACCUACUGCCAUCUUUUCACCCAUACCAGCCUUUGGAGUGCAUAGUAGAGGAGACUGAAGGCAAGCUGAAUGAACUGGGACAAAGAAUUAGUGCUAUUGAAAAAGCACAGCUUAAGUCACUGGAGUUAAUUCAAGGUGAACCUCUGAACAAAGAUAAGAUAGAAGAACUUAAAAAGAACAGAGAAGAGCAAGUCCAGAAGAAGAAGAAAAUAUUGAAAGAACUGCAGAAAGUGGAAAGGCAGUUGCAGAUGAAAACACAGCAGCAAUUUACCAAAGAAUACUUGGAAACCAAAGGUCAGAAAGACACAGUGUCUCUACACCAACAGUGCUCUCAUAGAGGAGUCUUCCCAGAAGGGGAAGGAGAUGGUAGUCUCCCAGAGGAUCACUUUUCAGAGUUACCUCAGGUUGACACAAUCUUAUUUAAAGAUAAUGAUGUUGAUGAUGAGCAACAGUCUCCACCAUCGGCAGAACAGAUUGAUUUUGUCCCAGUCCAGCCUUUAUCAUCUCCACAGUGUAACUUUUCCAGUGACUUAGGUUCUAAUGGGACAAAUUCUCUUGAACUUCAGAAAGUAUCAGGUAAUCAGCAGAUUGUAGGACAGCCUCAGAUUGCUAUUACUGGACAUGAUCAGGGGCUGUUAGUUCAAGAACCAGAUGGACUAAUGGUUGCAACUCCAGCUCAGACGCUUACCGACACUCUUGAUGACCUGAUAGCAGCUGUGAGUACCAGAGUGCCCACUGGUUCCAACAGUUCUUCUCAGACCACAGAGUGUCUUACACCUGAAUCCUGUUCGCAGACUACAAGCAAUGUGGCUUCCCAAUCGAUGCCUCCUGUGUAUCCUUCAGUUGACAUUGAUGCACAUACUGAGAGCAAUCAUGACACAGCAUUAACACUAGCUUGUGCAGGUGGUCAUGAAGAACUUGUAUCUGUGCUCAUUGCACGGGAUGCCAAAAUUGAACACAGAGACAAAAAAGGUUUCACACCACUAAUCCUGGCAGCAACAGCAGGGCAUGUUGGAGUUGUUGAAAUCCUUUUGGAUAAAGGUGGAGAUAUAGAAGCACAGUCUGAACGAACUAAGGAUACUCCGCUUUCAUUGGCAUGUUCUGGUGGACGUCAGGAGGUGGUAGACUUGCUGCUGGCUCGAGGUGCAAAUAAAGAACAUAGGAACGUAUCUGAUUAUACACCACUGAGUCUAGCUGCGUCUGGAGGAUAUGUUAAUAUCAUUAAGAUUCUGCUUAAUGCUGGGGCAGAAAUUAAUUCAAGGACUGGGAGUAAACUAGGUAUUUCUCCCCUGAUGUUGGCUGCAAUGAAUGGACAUGUUCCUGCAGUAAAAUUGCUGCUCGAUAUGGGUUCAGACAUUAAUGCCCAAAUAGAGACCAAUCGGAACACGGCUCUCACCCUGGCCUGUUUCCAGGGCCGAGCAGAAGUAGUGAGUUUGCUUCUGGACCGAAAAGCCAAUGUUGAACAUAGGGCAAAGACGGGUCUUACCCCCUUGAUGGAAGCAGCUUCUGGAGGGUAUGCAGAGGUUGGAAGAGUUCUUCUUGAUAAAGGAGCAGAUGUUAAUGCUCCCCCUGUGCCUUCCUCAAGAGAUACUGCUUUAACAAUAGCAGCAGACAAAGGUCACUACAAAUUUUGUGAACUCCUGAUUCAUAGGGGAGCCCACAUUGAUGUUCGUAACAAAAAGGGAAAUACGCCACUUUGGCUGGCAUCCAAUGGAGGUCAUUUUGAUGUUGUGCAGUUGCUAGUGCAAGCAGGUGCUGAUGUGGAUGCAGCAGAUAACCGGAAAAUCACACCUCUUAUGUCAGCAUUUCGCAAGGGUCAUGUAAAAGUUGUUCAAUAUUUGGUAAAGGAAGUAAAUCAGUUCCCUUCUGAUAUAGAAUGCAUGAGAUACAUAGCAACAAUUACAGAUAAGGAACUGUUGAAAAAAUGUCAUCAAUGUGUCGAAACCAUUGUGAAGGCUAAAGACCAGCAAGCUGCAGAAGCAAAUAAGAAUGCGAGUAUUCUUUUAAAGGAACUUGAUCUGGAAAAGUCAAGAGAAGAGAGCAGAAAGCAGGCUCUUGCUGCUAAAAGAGAAAAAAGAAAAGAAAAGAGAAAAAAGAAAAAAGAGGAACAGAAAAGGAAACAGGAAGAAGAUGAAGAAAACAAACCUAAGGAGAAUUCGGAACUACCAGAGGAUGAAGAUGAAGAGGAGAAUGAUGAAGAUGUGGAGCAAGAAGUUCCCAUAGAACCUCCUAGUGCAACCACCACCACUACGAUUGGAAUCUCUGCAACAUCUGCAACAUUCACAAAUGUGUUUGGGAAAAAAAGGGCCAAUGUGGUGACAACUCCCAGCACCAAUCGGAAAAAUAAGAAGAACAAAACAAAAGAAACCCCUCCUACAGCACAUUUAAUUUUACCAGAACAACAUAUGUCUUUAGCCCAACAAAAGGCAGAUAAAAAUAAAAUAAAUGGAGAACCUAGAGGUGGUGGUGCAGGUGGGAAUAGUGAUUCAGAUAACUUGGACAGCACAGACUGCAACAGUGAGAGUAGCAGUGGUGGUAAAAGCCAAGAGUUAAAUUUUGUGAUGGAUGUGAAUUCCUCUAAAUACCCCUCACUGCUCCUUCAUUCCCAAGAAGAAAAGACAAGUACUGCUACUUCCAAAACUCAGACACGACUUGAAGGUGAAGUGACUCCUAAUUCCUUGUCAACCAGCUACAAGACAGUGUCAUUGCCAUUAAGCUCUCCAAACAUAAAGCUGAAUCUCACUAGCCCUAAAAGGGGUCAGAAAAGAGAAGAAGGGUGGAAAGAAGUUGUACGAAGGUCAAAGAAAUUGUCUGUUCCAGCCUCAGUGGUGUCGAGGAUAAUGGGAAGAGGAGGAUGCAACAUCACUGCAAUACAGGAUGUUACUGGUGCCCAUAUUGAUGUGGAUAAACAAAAAGAUAAGAAUGGCGAGAGAAUGAUCACAAUAAGGGGUGGCACAGAAUCAACAAGAUAUGCAGUUCAACUAAUCAAUGCACUCAUUCAAGAUCCUGCUAAGGAACUGGAAGACUUGAUUCCUAAAAAUCAUAUCAGAACACCUGCCAGCACCAAAUCAAUUCAUGCUAACUUCUCAUCUGGAGUAGGUACCACAGCAGCUUCCAGUAAAAAUGCAUUUCCUUUGGGUGCUCCAACUCUUGUAACUUCACAGGCAACAACGUUAUCUACGUUCCAGCCCGCUAAUAAACUUAAUAAGAAUGUUCCAACAAAUGUACGUUCUUCUUUCCCAGUUUCUCUACCCUUAGCUUAUCCUCACCCUCAUUUUGCCCUGCUGGCUGCUCAAACUAUGCAACAGAUUCGGCAUCCUCGCUUACCCAUGGCCCAGUUUGGAGGAACCUUCUCACCUUCUCCUAACACAUGGGGACCAUUCCCAGUGAGACCUGUGAAUCCUGGCAACACAAAUAGCUCUCCAAAGCAUAAUAACACAAGCCGUCUACCUAACCAGAACGGGACUGUUUUACCCUCAGAGUCUGCUGGACUAGCUACUGCCAGUUGUCCUAUCACUGUCUCUUCUGUAGUUGCUGCCAGUCAGCAACUGUGUGUCACUAAUACCCGGACUCCUUCAUCAGUCAGAAAGCAGUUGUUUGCCUGUGUGCCUAAGACAAGUCCUCCAGCAACAGUGAUUUCUUCUGUGACAAGCACUUGUAGUUCCCUGCCUUCUGUCUCCUCUGCACCUAUCACUAGCGGGCAAGCUCCCACCACAUUUCUACCUGCAAGUACUUCUCAAGCACAGCUUUCUUCACAAAAGAUGGAGUCUUUCUCUGCUGUGCCACCCACCAAAGAGAAAGUGUCCACACAGGACCAGCCCAUGGCAAACCUAUGUACCCCAUCUUCAACUGCAAACAGUUGCAGUAGCUCUGCCAGCAACACCCCGGGAGCUCCAGAAACUCACCCAUCCAGUAGUCCCACUCCUACUUCCAGUAACACACAAGAGGAGGCACAGCCAUCCAGUGUGUCUGAUUUAAGUCCUAUGUCAAUGCCUUUUGCAUCUAACUCAGAACCUGCUCCAUUGACUUUGACAUCACCCAGAAUGGUUGCUGCUGAUAAUCAGGACACCAGUAAUUUACCUCAGUUAGCUGUACCAGCACCUCGAGUUUCUCAUCGAAUGCAGCCCAGAGGUUCUUUUUACUCCAUGGUACCAAAUGCAACUAUUCACCAGGAUCCCCAGUCUAUUUUUGUUACGAAUCCAGUUACUUUAACACCACCUCAAGGCCCACCAGCUGCAGUGCAGCUUUCUUCAGCUGUGAACAUUAUGAAUGGUUCUCAGAUGCACAUAAACCCAGCAAAUAAGUCUUUGCCACCUACAUUUGGCCCAGCCACACUUUUCAAUCACUUCAGCAGUCUUUUUGAUAGUAGUCAGGUGCCAGCUAACCAGGGCUGGGGAGAUGGUCCACUGUCCUCACGAGUUGCUACAGAUGCCUCUUUCACUGUUCAGUCAGCGUUCCUGGGUAACUCAGUGCUUGGACACUUGGAAAACAUGCACCCUGAUAACUCAAAGGCACCUGGCUUCAGACCACCUUCCCAGCGAGUUUCUACUAGUCCAGUUGGGUUACCAUCCAUUGACCCAUCAGGCAGCUCCCCAUCUUCCUCUUCUGCUCCUCUGGCAAGUUUUUCCGGCAUACCAGGAACAAGGGUUUUCCUGCAAGGGCCAGCUCCUGUUGGGACUCCUAGUUUCAACAGACAACAUUUUUCUCCCCAUCCUUGGACAAGCGCCUCAAACUCAUCCACUUCUGCCCCACCAACGUUGGGCCAACCAAAAGGAGUCAGUGCCAGUCAAGAUCGAAAGAUACCUCCCCCAAUUGGAACAGAGAGACUGGCCCGAAUUCGGCAAGGAGGGUCUGUUGCACAAGCCCCGGCGGGGACCAGUUUUGUCGCUCCCGUUGGACACAGUGGAAUCUGGUCAUUUGGUGUCAAUGCUGUGUCAGAAGGCUUAUCAGGUUGGUCGCAAUCUGUGAUGGGGAACCAUCCAAUGCAUCAACAAUUAUCAGACCCAAGCACAUUCUCCCAACAUCAGCCAAUGGAGAGAGAUGAUUCUGGAAUGGUAGCCCCCUCUAACAUUUUUCAUCAGCCUAUGGCAAGUGGUUUUGUGGAUUUUUCUAAAGGUCUGCCAAUUUCCAUGUAUGGAGGCACCAUAAUACCCUCUCAUCCUCAGCUUGCUGAUGUUCCAGGAGGCCCUCUGUUUAAUGGACUUCACAAUCCAGAUCCUGCUUGGAACCCUAUGAUAAAAGUUAUCCAAAAUUCAACUGAAUGCACUGAUGCCCAGCAGGCCAGUCUGCUUCCUUCAGUCCCUGCUCUCAAAGGGGAAAUCCCAUCACCUCAGCUAACCAGACCGAAGAAGAGAAUUGGACGGCCGAUGGUGGCCUCUCCUAACCAGAGGCACCAGGAUCAUCUACGACCGAAAGUUCCUGCUGGAGUGCAAGAACUCACCCAUUGCCCGGACACCCCCCUGCUGCCUCCCUCAGAUUCCCGGGGUCACAACUCCUCCAACAGCCCCUCUCUCCAAGCUGGAGGAGCUGAAGGAGCAGGAGACAGAGGAAGAGAUACCCGAUGACGCACAAUUUGAAAUGGACAUCUAAUCCAGUGCAGAUGACCUGGCAUGUGGAGUUACAGAGGGAUCCCUCAUGCCACUGCUGCCACCACCUCUUCCUGGGGCAUCCAAAGGCCAGCUGGCCUCAUCUAAUCUGGAAGGGAGUGACUUGUUAGUUCCAGGCCUCCUUUAGUUCUGAGGCAGCUAGACCAGGGAUAGGAGUGGGCAACUUGCCAAGCCCUUAACUCUACUUCCUCUUCAGUCUGUGGUACUCCUCCUAACCCUAAACCCUCUAUGCUCAGGGGCUGGAACUGGGGAAUGGAGUAAGUCACCUUCUGACUGCUUAGUAAACAUUCAAAGAAA